GUAUAUGCUGAUCUUGCAUGCAGAGUAGACGCUGCACCGGUCUCCUUUUGGUCCCGGUGUCUGUGUCACACACGGCGGGUCCUGCCGAAAUGCACUUCUAGGAAAGGGAAUGACCUGCCCGUGUGAUAAUGCCUCGUCAGUGUUCUUGGGCUUUUAUGCCCAGCUCUCUCCUGUUUUUAUAAGUCGCAGCUCCGCAAACUCACUGAAGCAACUCGUUUACCAUAGUUUUUACUACAUGUACCUGAGGCCGUUAGAUUUGUCUGUGUUAAGGAUUUGAAAGGGUAAGCUAAAGGAUCUGAAGGGAAGUUUAAGUGAGGCCUUAAAAAUAUUUCCAGCAAAGGGGCAUAGUGUGAGAAUAUGCGACUGAUUUGAGAAGACUGGUUCAAAAGUUCUGGUGGGUUUGGAAAUAUUAUCAAAGAUUGUUCUAUUAACUUUCCCAGAGUAAAUUAUCUGUAUUUCAUUUGCUAUGGUUCUGCCUGAGACCAGUCUACCUUUUUAGAAGGAAGUUUAUUGUUUUAAAGUCAGUUUGGAGGGAAAGUACAGAUUGAUAAUAGCAAUUUAUUGAUGGUAGGAGUCAAUUAACUUUCUCUUCCAGUCUGCCCCCCCCCAGUUGUCUUGAUAUUAAAACUAUUAAAAUUCCCUAUCACUGAUGCUACUAUCAUAAAAUUUUCUAAAAUUAUCAUAAUUUACAUAUAGUUGAUGGACCGUAGAUGGAGUUCUCUCAUACAUUGACCCUAAGUCUUUUAAUUACAAAUAUUAGUACCCAAAAAAGUGUACCCUAUAUUAAUCCAGUAACUAGUUUUUAAAAGUCAAAAUGCCAGAAGGAAACAGUGGAAUCUUGAUGACAUAAUGCAAGGGAAGACCGGAGUCAAUGCAGUGUUAAAGACGCCCUCAGCCUCUGGGAUGUCAUUGUUUAGCGCUUAAGGGAAGACUAUAGAAAGCACUGAUACUGAUUUAAAAUGAGAUAUUUCUCUGCCUUCACUGGGGGAAAAAAUGUUUCUGACUUAUUUUGCUGUGCUCAAUUGACAACCAUCAAAACUUAGGUAACUUUUAAUAAACUCACAGUUUCUAAUAUUUUUAAGUGGCUGUGUGUCUGCAUCUGCUGCCACAGAUAAAAUAUAACCUUUGUAGGUGAAUUUAAUUUAGGACUUUUCUGAAAGUUCAGUCAGAGGAUAGGUAAUUUGUGUGUCUUUUAAAAGCACUUAGCCCCGAGGUUGUUGUUUUUAAUACAUCUUAUUUAAAUACGGAAAUGUGUUGCCCUUAUGCCUUUUUAUUUCAUGGAAGCCAAAUGCGUCUUUUCUCCCAAAGUAUACUAGAAAAUGAAGACGCUUGGUAAUGGUAGUGAUCUGUACAUCAGAUUUCAGUCUUUCUGUCACUUGCGUGUAUGAAUCCAUUUAGCAAGUUUGCUUUUGGCAGUAAAGCCCCACGUGCAGGAAGACAAACAGCUGCUCACUCAUUAUCCAAAGUAUACUUUGUAAGAAUUAGGGCAUCAAAAAUUGGAUCCUAAGCACCAAUAUAUAUUAAAGUUCAGUACAACUUGUAGUGUUUAAGUACAAGAAAUAAAAAUUGAGCCUGAACUUUUGGCAUAUAGUGGGAAGAAAUUAGGUUUACCGCUGUUAAUAAUUCAGAGUGCUUAGGAAAAUCGGUUUUUAUUUACUUAUGUUAAAAAUACUAAGGGUUCUGUAACCAUUAAAAACUAAAAUACUAACCUGUAGAUGUUGAAAAAAUCCUAGACACUAGUCUCUGCCACGUGACUGUUCUUCUUUUCUAUUUAUUUUACCCAAUAAUUAGGCUUUUACAAUGUAAGUAAUAAAGAGAAAAAUCUCUAGUAUCACUUUAGAGCACAUUGAUUCAUAAAUAGCCCAUAAAUUUUGUACUCAGCAACCCAUAAAAUACACAUGCAUGAUUCACAUAAUCAAAUAGUAACGAAAGUUACAAAAUGAAAAGUGAAGCAGCUCUACCCCAAGUCCUUCCCCCAAUAUAACCAUGAACAGUCUUAAAUCUAAUGCCGCUGUCUAAAACUGACUAGUUAUUCAAAUGAAUCAAUAUUUUCCCCUUUCCAGAGGCAGAAAUUAAUACAGAUUCAAGUGUUCACUAUCAAGUCGGAAUUGUUAAUAUGUGAAAUACUACUGUUAAAGGCAGGAAAGGCUUUAUUAAGGACAAGAAGACAAACUAGGAGAAGGAGCUACUCAAGACCUUCCGAUUAUCUUUACAAAAAGGCAACUACACCUAGAAGAUUCUGCAGCCACACACAUUCUGCCUUCACUUGAGGUCAACUGCCUUCACCAAGGUAUCCGUUACAGCACUGAUGUGAGUGUAGAUGAAGUAAAAGCUUUGGCUUCUCUGAUGACAUACAAGUGUGCAGUGGUUGAUGUGCCGUUUGGGGGUGCUAAAGCUGGUGUUAAGAUCAAUCCCAAGAACUAUACUGAUAAUGAAUUGGAAAAGAUCACAAGGAGGUUCACCAUGGAGCUAGCAAAAAAGGGCUUUAUUGGUCCUGGCAUUGAUGUGCCUGCUCCAGACAUGAGCACAGGUGAGCGGGAGAUGUCCUGGAUCGCUGAUACCUAUGCCAGCACCAUAGGGCACUAUGAUAUUAAUGCACACGCCUGUGUUACUGGUAAACCCAUCAGCCAAGGGGGAAUCCAUGGACGCAUCUCUGCUACUGGCCGUGGUGUCUUCCAUGGGAUUGAAAAUUUCAUCAAUGAAGCUUCUUACAUGAGCAUUUUAGGAAUGACACCAGGGUUUGGAGAUAAAACAUUUGUUGUUCAGGGAUUUGGUAAUGUGGGCCUACACUCUAUGAGAUAUUUACAUCGUUUUGGUGCUAAAUGUAUUGCUGUUGGUGAGUCUGAUGGGAGUAUAUGGAAUCCAGAUGGUAUUGACCCAAAGGAACUGGAAGACUUCAAAUUGCAACAUGGGUCCAUUCUGGGCUUCCCCAAGGCAAAGCCCUAUGAAGGAAGCAUCUUGGAGGCCGACUGUGACAUACUGAUCCCAGCUGCCAGUGAGAAGCAGUUGACCAAAUCCAACGCACCCAGAGUCAAAGCCAAGAUCAUUGCUGAAGGUGCCAAUGGGCCAACAACUCCAGAAGCUGACAAGAUCUUCCUGGAGAGAAACAUUAUGGUUAUUCCAGAUCUCUACUUGAAUGCUGGAGGAGUGACAGUAUCUUACUUUGAGUGGCUGAAGAAUCUAAAUCAUGUCAGCUAUGGCCGUUUGACCUUCAAAUAUGAAAGGGAUUCUAACUACCACUUGCUCAUGUCUGUUCAAGAGAGUUUAGAAAGAAAAUUUGGAAAGCAUGGUGGAACUAUUCCCAUUGUACCCACGGCAGAGUUCCAAGACAGGAUAUCGGGUGCAUCUGAGAAAGACAUCGUGCACUCUGGCUUGGCAUACACAAUGGAGCGUUCUGCCAGGCAAAUUAUGCGCACAGCCAUGAAGUAUAACCUGGGAUUGGACCUGAGAACAGCUGCCUAUGUUAAUGCCAUUGAGAAAGUCUUCAAAGUGUACAAUGAAGCUGGUGUGACCUUCACAUAGAUGGAUCAUGGCUGACUUCCUCACUAUCCUCUUCACAUGUAACUUCUGCAGACCUAUCACAAGUUUACAUGUAACCACAGAAAUCCCUUUCUCUCCUGACUCAUUAAUAAUGGAUACCAUUCUCAACAAGUCAAUCCAAGUCAGCCCGUUAAGGAGAAAGAAAUUAAGGUUAGCGGAUCAUGUACAAGCUGAGUGUGAAAGUAGAAAUCACCUACACCAGAGAGCCAUUUUGGUAUUUUGCCUUUAAAUAAAAAGCCUCCUUUAUCUGGCUGUGCAGCCUUGCUCUGUGGCUUUUCCCAACACAAUCAGUGCUAGUGCUGGGGAGGAACAGUCAAGAGCAGUCAGUUGCUUGCUUAUUUUUUCUGGAUGAGUCUGGGACACACUGUAACUUUAACACAUUUAAGAAGUAGGUGUGUGGCCUUUUCAGAAGGUGGCAUGGUCCUCAAGUGAGUUCUUAGUAUUUUAUAUCAGCAAAAUAAUUCAAUUUUGCAGGUUGCAAACAAAUAUAAAACCUGUUUCUGUUUAUGAAUAUUAUUCUUUUAGAAUAGAAUAAGUACAUGCUGCUGUAAUAAAAUUGCCUUUAAUCACUUAACAAGCCUAACCUUGACUCAAACAGUGAAUGCCUAUAGAAAUAAUAAAUGAAAAAAACUAGUAUUUUUAUAUCAUAAAACAAUGUCAUUUAUAGCUUAUCAUUCAUGUAUUGUCCAGCAGACAUUAAAAGCCCUGUGGAUAAUUAAGUUAUCUUCAUACCUGCAAAAUGGUGGAGGCUAUUUUCAUUAAAACUGUCAGAAUUUGCUUACUAUAAUUAUGAUACAGUCCAAAGAAUGCAGUCACUUUUUAUCAUGUUAACUAAUUGUUCUCUUUUGAAGAUCUAUGGUUGACUAAUUAAACAAUAAUUCAAGUAGAGUGUCCCAGAAAAAAACCACUUGGGCUCCCUGUUUGGAGUCUGGCUGGCUCUGAGCAUUGCCAAUGGCCCCUACUCACCUGACUUUGUAUCCUCUCCUUUUAGAGGCUUUGCAUUCUGCACCCAGCUUCACUAACAGUGGGCUGAAAACAUCCUUGGGUUGAGUGUUUCAUUUGGGAGUUAUUUGGCCAGGGCCUUUUGAACAGUAGUGUCCCCAUGAAGUGCUAGAUAAUAUAUGUGUAAGAGUCAGCUUUUUUUUUUUUUUUAACUCUAACACCCUUCAGAAAUUUCUAACUACUUUGUAACUGCAUGGCUUAACCUGGUGAUAAAAGCAGUUAUUAAAAGUCUACGUUUUCCAAAACUUACGUUUCUUUUCUGUGUUUUUACAUGUGGUAGUUUCUCUUUUCAUAAGUUAUAAUACUGCAAUUGGAUUUCUGAAAUGUUUAUAGCGACCACCUGUAUAACAUUUCCUUCCACUUUAUUGUGAGCUGCCCAGAUUUUAUUCUUGAAUUGUUUUUUUUUUUUUUGUUCGGUGCUUUACACGUUCAGAGAAACUUCCCGAGUAACGAACUAUAGAAAUGAUCCCUGAAAGCAUAGUCUUUAUUCUCGAAUUAUUUUGUAUUUUAUUAAAUAAUAUGAACAGCU